GCUCGGCCUCCCCCAUCCCCCGGUAACGGUCGCUGGUGAGUUUAAAUGAGCAGGGGCUGGCCGGGCCGGAGCCGCUACAGGGGGGGCCUGAGGCACUGCAGAAAGUGGGCCUGAGCCUCGAGGAUGACGGUGCUGCAGGAACCCGUCCAGGCUGCUAUAUGGCAAGCACUAAACCACUAUGCUUACCGAGAUGCGGUUUUCCUCGCAGAACGCCUUUAUGCAGAAGUACACUCAGAAGAAGCCUUGUUUUUACUGGCAACCUGUUAUUACCGCUCAGGAAAGGCAUAUAAAGCAUAUAGACUCUUGAAAGGACACAGUUGUACUACACCGCAAUGCAAAUACCUGCUUGCAAAAUGUUGUGUUGAUCUCAGCAAGCUUGCAGAAGGGGAACAAAUCUUAUCUGGUGGAGUGUUUAAUAAGCAGAAAAGCCAUGAUGAUAUUGUUACUGAGUUUGGUGAUUCAGCUUGCUUUACUCUUUCAUUGUUGGGACAUGUAUAUUGCAAGACAGAUCGGCUUGCCAAAGGAUCAGAAUGUUACCAAAAGAGCCUUAGUUUAAAUCCUUUCCUCUGGUCUCCCUUUGAAUCAUUAUGUGAAAUAGGUGAAAAGCCAGAUCCUGACCAAACAUUUAAAUUCACAUCUUUACAGAACUUUAGCAACUGUCUGCCCAACUCUUGCACAACACAAGUACCUAAUCAUAGUUUAUCUCACAGACAGCCUGAGACAGUUCUUACGGAAACACCCCAGGACACAAUUGAAUUAAACAGAUUGAAUUUAGAAUCUUCCAAUUCAAAGUACUCCUUGAAUACAGAUUCCUCAGUGUCUUAUAUUGAUUCAGCUGUAAUUUCACCUGAUACUGUCCCACUGGGAACAGGAACUUCCAUAUUAUCUAAACAGGUUCAAAAUAAACCAAAAACUGGUCGAAGUUUAUUAGGAGGACCAGCAGCUCUUAGUCCAUUAACCCCAAGUUUUGGGAUUUUGCCAUUAGAAACCCCAAGUCCUGGAGAUGGAUCCUAUUUACAAAACUACACUAAUACACCUCCUGUAAUUGAUGUGCCAUCCACCGGAGCCCCUUCAAAAAAGACUUUUCGUGUUUUACAGUCUGUUGCCAGAAUCGGCCAAACUGGAACAAAGUCUGUCUUCUCACAGAGUGGAAAUAGCCGAGAGGUAACUCCAAUUCUUGCACAAACACAAAGUUCUGGUCCACAAACAAGUACAACACCUCAGGUAUUGAGCCCCACUAUUACAUCUCCCCCAAACGCACUGCCUCGAAGAAGUUCACGACUCUUUACUAGUGACAGCUCCACAACCAAGGAGAAUAGCAAAAAAUUAAAAAUGAAGUUUCCACCUAAAAUCCCAAACAGAAAAACAAAAAGUAAAACUAAUAAAGGAGGAAUAACUCAACCUAACAUAAAUGAUAGCCUGGAAAUUACAAAAUUGGACUCUUCCAUCAUUUCAGAAGGGAAAAUAUCCACAAUCACACCUCAGAUUCAGGCCUUUAAUCUACAAAAAGCAGCAGCAGAAGGUUUGAUGAGCCUUCUUCGUGAAAUGGGGAAAGGUUAUUUAGCUUUGUGUUCAUACAACUGCAAAGAAGCUAUAAAUAUUUUGAGCCAUCUACCUUCUCACCACUACAAUACUGGUUGGGUACUGUGCCAAAUUGGAAGGGCCUAUUUUGAACUUUCAGAGUACAUGCAAGCUGAAAGAAUAUUCUCAGAGGUUAGAAGGAUUGAGAAUUAUAGAGUUGAAGGCAUGGAGAUCUACUCUACAACACUUUGGCAUCUUCAAAAAGAUGUUGCUCUUUCAGUUCUGUCAAAAGACUUAACAGACAUGGAUAAAAAUUCGCCAGAGGCCUGGUGUGCUGCAGGGAACUGUUUCAGUCUGCAACGGGAACAUGAUAUUGCAAUUAAAUUCUUCCAGAGAGCUAUCCAAGUUGAUCCAAAUUACGCUUAUGCCUAUACUCUAUUAGGGCAUGAGUUUGUCUUAACUGAAGAAUUGGACAAAGCAUUAGCUUGUUUUCGAAAUGCUAUCAGAGUCAAUCCUAGACAUUAUAAUGCAUGGUAUGGUUUAGGAAUGAUUUAUUACAAGCAAGAAAAAUUCAGCCUUGCAGAAAUGCAUUUCCAAAAAGCGCUUGAUAUCAACCCUCAAAGUUCAGUUUUACUUUGCCACAUUGGAGUAGUUCAACAUGCACUGAAAAAAUCAGAGAAGGCUUUGGAUACCCUAAACAAAGCCAUUGUCAUUGAUCCCAAGAACCCUCUAUGCAAAUUUCACAGAGCCUCAGUUUUAUUUGCAAAUGAAAAAUAUAAGUCUGCUUUACAAGAACUUGAAGAAUUGAAACAAAUUGUUCCCAAAGAAUCCCUCGUUUACUUCUUAAUAGGAAAGGUUUACAAGAAGUUAGGUCAAACGCACCUCGCCCUGAUGAAUUUCUCUUGGGCUAUGGAUUUAGAUCCUAAAGGAGCCAAUAACCAGAUUAAAGAGGCAAUUGAUAAGCGUUAUCUUCCAGAUGAUGAGGAGCCAAUAACCCAAGAAGAACAGAUCAUGGGAACAGAUGAAUCCCAGGAGAGCAGCAUGACAGAUGCGGAUGACACACAACUUCAUGCAGCUGAAAGUGAUGAAUUUUAACUUCUGGAAAUCAGACUUUUACAACUGGAUGUGUGACUAGUGCUGACGUGUUUCUUGUCCCUCUGUAUACUGAGUCUUUACUCUUGAGCUGGCGGUGUCAUCGUCCGUCACUUAUACCAUGAGUGUGCCACUUUCAUUGGACCCUGACUGUAUACAGAAUGAAAGGCAGUGCAAUAUUUAGCUGCUAACAAGACUGGCUCUUUUACCAGUAUGAAUGACAAUUUAUGGGGGGUAGGGUGGGGAACUUUCUUUUCUGUUUUUCUUUAAUCUCCCUUUGUUGGAAAGUAUCAUGAAAGGAAGAGUUAUGCUUUAUCUUGAAGGAACCAUUAGAUAUGGAAAAUAGUGAUGAACCAGAGUUUCUUGGUUGCUUUUUCAAAAAUUUGUUUUUAUUUGGUUCUGUUCCUGAUAAACAGAGUAACUGACCUUCAUUUCUAGGUUCUUCAAGAAUGGUGUUUGCAAGUGCCAGAUGGAACAAUAAAAGACGUUGCCUAUAACAGUGACUUGAUUGCCAAGGAAUGUAAAUUACCUUAAACUUGCAGUAUCUCCCAUAAACAAAUGUAAUGGGCAUAUUGGGACUCGUAUGUAGGAAUCAAAUAUCCCUCCAUACAGUGUACUCUUAUUCUUGGCAAGAAUGCUUUAAUGUCUAACCAAGAAUUUUAAUUUAUUCAUCUUGCUUCAAAGUGUUGAUCAUUGUUGUCUUGGUAUUGCAAACUUUAAAAUUGUUUCUUACCAUAUUGCCUCUUCUCUUUGAGCUCUGUGGGAUCACCUUUAACAUUCAGAGAUGAUAGAGUGGUUCCCCACUGAGAAGCCAAAACAAGGCCCUUAAUAACCCCUUAAGUUCACCAUAUGAAUCAGAAGGAGAACACUAAAGUGGAGAGACUUUUAAGAGAUCAUGAUAGUGAAAGCCUUAAUAUAAUCAGAAUUGUACCAUAACCUUGAAUCUAUAUUUGUUCAAAACAUCCCUUUGACUUUUCUAAGUGUUUGCUUAAGCAGAGUGUAAGAAUGUGUGGUUACCUUUGGUUGAGAUCCUUUCCAUUCUUUUUGACUCUCUGCUUCAGAUUUUUUCAGUAGUGUGAGUCACCAAAACAUUUACUAAGAGUAAUUGGGUUUAGGAUGUUGGAAAUUUUUAGCUUGGGGGAAAAAACAUUCUUAUGAAGGAGAUAGGUUCUCUUCUGAGUUUGUCAUAAUAUAGAUUGGUGUCUUUGGAAAAUGGCCACAAUUUUAAGAAUUCAAUUAUGCAUAUAAAAUGAUAAUUAUUGGAAUUCCACAGUAACAGAUUUAAACAGUCUUAAAUUGUUUAUCUCCUUUACUGUAAUGUAUUGAAAUUUUUAGAGAAAUUUUAGUUGUUAACAUUUUAUUAAGUGCCAGUGUCAGAAUAUAACAAAUUAUAGUUUCUUAUGAAUGACAGGCCUACAGUUAUUAUUCUGGAUUAUUUGAUGGAGGACAAACUUACCUGUAUUUGUUAGUCAAGCUGUGAAAAUAAGGUGGAUUACAAAAGAUGUGAAAAAAAUUUUAGUCUGUAGACUCAGUAAUUUUCUAUAAUUUACUGUUAAUCUCAUUUGAACAUGGAUUAGGUACAAUUUAUAAAUUAAUUCAAGUCAGGGUCUUUAGGUAUCAGGUGCCAGAGAGAUAUUUAACAGAUUUCCCUACCUAAAUUUAUGUAUAUGUACUGUCUAAAACAAUACUUUUUUAAAAAAAAGGAACAGUUGGGAGAAAAUAAAUAUAAUGAAAAAUUCCCAGAGGCUAGCACUUGGAUUCUAACACGUAUGCUAUUGUAUUAUCCAUUAGUUCUGUAAUAUUUAAUUUUAGAUUCUUUUAUUUUUUUAAUUGGCAAAGCACAAGGUGCUGUAUAACAGUGUCAUUUAGAGUUUUAUAGAAAGCUUCAACCUGAGUUCUGCGUUAUAAAGCCUGGAGAAAGCUAAGCUUAGAACAUAACUUGCUGAAGUAUAAUUAUCUUUUUGUAGCAGGAAUUUAUGUGCCAGAGGUGAGAGUCUUUCUGGUACUGAUUUUUUGAGACCAAGGAUAAAAGGAUCGUUUUGUAAGACAUGCCAUGGCAAUGGCUGGUUGGGGGACAGUUUCCGCCCAAGCUUGGCCUAUUUUAUUUUUCCUCAUACCUACUUUCAAAGUCAUUUAGGUAUUUGAAGCCUUAUUUCCCACGUAGUAACACUUUCUGGCUUUUGCAGUUUCUUUUUUUGUUUGGUUUUGUUUUUUGCAUGGAAUGGGGAUCAAACAACCCGAAGAAGAACACAUUUUGAUCAAGCAAAAUGUUUGCUUCAAAUUUCAGAAGUUUAUUUUACAGAAAUUAAAUUAAGUAGUUUGACAUCCUUUUCUCUGUUUCACACAUAUAUUAGGUUGGUGCAUAAGUAAUUGUGGUUUUUGCCAUGACUUUUAUGGCAAAACCUGCAAUUACUUUUGCACCAACUUAAUACAUCUAUAUACAUAUAUAUAUACGCGCACACACUUGUUCAGAAGUUAUGUUGUGGCCUUGGAUUUGUUUUUCCCCUUGGAAAUGGUUCUUAACUCUGGGAUUUUAGAAGGUUAGAAUAUUUUUUCAAGAGAACAGUGGUACUCAAAAGAAUGAAAGGUGGUCCCUACAUUUUCUGUAUUCAUCACUUAAAAUUUUUAAUUUUUCCGAGAACUACAAGUAACAUUUGAACCAUGCUGCUGUUGUACCUUAAACAAAAACUCAGUGAUAACCAGUAUUUAGUCUAUUAAAAAUGCUCUUUUUGAAGAAAAAAGUUUGGAAGUCUCUGAUUAGCCAGAGUAUAGUAUGAGUCUUCACUGAGAAAUAUGGUGACCCAUUUUCUUUGUGAAAACCUGGGAAAAUGCAAGUGUGGGUAUGAAGUGUGUGUUCUGUUUGCAUUGAAACAAUGUAAUUUUGUGUCUUCUUUUUGCUUUAACUGACUUAUUUCAGAAAUUGUACAGUGUUGAGGGGGAAAGUCUUUUCUGUUAAUAUAUUUGCAAUUCAUUAAAGGAUAUGGAAAAUCCAAAUAAGUUACUUUUGAAAGCAAUUUAUAAUCAAGUUGUUAAAGCUAUAUGAAAGCUGUGCCAUCUGUAUUUUAAUAAGAAGGCACAGAAAAACAGAGAUACAGUUUUAUGUUUCACAAAAAACUAGAGCAAUGUUUAUCUAAUUUUUUAAAACUUACACUCUUAAUAUAUUUAUAUUUUUAAACGGUCAUACUCUUUUUUAGUAUUAUUUGGAAUAUCAAAAUAAAUACUAUGACAAAAACAA